GUCCGUAGUCAAGUUGCCGGUGGAAUUGGCCCAGGAUGACAGCUGGAGAAUGGAGUCAGGUACGGGGAGCGGCUUUGAGUGGAACCGUGUGAAAGAGCCGGGGUGGGUAGUCGCUGGCGGGUCGUUGAGUCGGCCAUAUGAAACAGGUUCGGGGGCAGGGCAAGAGUUAUGAGAGCCUAAAGGUCCUGUCCCCCGGGGUUCCUGACCUGCAGUGGCAGGCGGAAGGGACAAGGGUUGGAGCUGAGUACUACCUACUGAGCUCGAACCGGUGACUGUGGCUACCCUCCCCCUCCCUGCCACCGCCUAGGGAGUGGAAAGAAGUGGGGGUUAAUUACUCUGACAUCUCGGCGGUGUGGCAUCAGGACAGGGUUCUACCACAGCAGUGAUAGCAUAUGGCACCGUACUGAGGUGAUGUGCCAGGGUGAUGCCAAAGGCAGGGUGUGAUGCCGUGGGAGCCACCUGAUAUCUAAGAGACCUCGUUUUAUCCAAGUAUGAAGAUCAGAUUACUAUUUUCACUGACUACCUAGAAGAAUAUCCAGAUACAGAUGAGCUGGUAUGGAUCUUAGGGAAGCAGCAUCUCCUUAAAACAGAUUGGGAAAGAAAGACCUUUUAACCUGAAACUGCUAACAGCCCAGCACCCAGAUAAAGCCAGAGCUUGGAAAGAGGCAGCUCUGAGAUUUGUGUCUUUCUGAGGAGACAUCCUCUUCAGAGGCCCUCACUUAGCGUGGAGGAAGGAACAGGAAGAGGCUGAUGAAAAGGCAGGAGAGGAAGUUAGGCAUUGUGGAGCUCCUCCUGAGCCUGGCUUCAUUAUUUUGAUUGGAGAAUUCUGAACAGUGGAAAGCCUGGAGCUAGCAAUUAGGAGACCUUUUGUAUUCAGACUCUUCUAACUCAGAAAAAUCUAAGCUGUUGUCUGAUAUAAGUGCUCGUCUAUGGUUUACAUACAGAAGGAAAUUUUCACCAAUUGGUGGAACGGGCCCUUCAUCAGAUGCUGGUUGGGGAUGUAUGCUACGCUGUGGACAGAUGAUGCUGGCUCAAGCCCUUAUCUGUAGACACUUGGGAAGGGACUGGAGCUGGGAGAAACAAAAAGAACAACCCAAAGAAUACCAACGCAUCCUACAGUGCUUCUUAGAUAGAAAAGAUUGUUGCUACUCUAUCCAUCAAAUGGCACAAAUGGGUGUAGGAGAAGGGAAAUCAAUUGGAGAAUGGUUUGGACCAAAUACAGUUGCACAGGUGUUAAAAAAACUUGCUUUAUUUGACGAAUGGAAUUCCUUGGCUGUUUAUGUUUCAAUGGAUAACACAGUGGUCAUUGAAGAUAUCAAAAAAAUGUGCCGUGUCCUUCCCUUGAGUGCUGACACAGCUGGUGACAGGCCUCCCGAUUCUUUAACUGCUUCAAACCAGAGUAAGGGCACCUCUGCCUACUGCUCAGCCUGGAAACCCCUGCUGCUCAUUGUGCCCCUUCGCCUGGGCAUAAACCAAAUCAAUCCUGUCUAUGUUGAUGCAUUCAAAGAGUGUUUUAAGAUGCCACAGUCUUUAGGGGCAUUAGGAGGAAAACCAAAUAACGCGUAUUAUUUCAUAGGAUUCUUAGGUGACGAGCUCAUCUUCUUGGACCCUCAUACAACCCAGACCUUUGUUGACACUGAAGAGAAUGGAACGGUUAAUGACCAGACUUUCCAUUGCCUGCAGUCCCCACAGCGAAUGAACAUCCUAAACCUGGAUCCUUCAGUUGCAUUGGGAUUUUUCUGCAAAGAAGAAAAAGACUUUGAUAACUGGUGUAGCCUUGUUCAGAAGGAAAUUCUAAAGGAGAAUUUAAGGAUGUUUGAAUUAGUUCAGAAACAUCCAUCACACUGGCCUCCCUUUGUACCUCCAGCCAAGCCAGAAGUGACAACCACUGGGGCAGAAUUCAUUGACUCUACUGAGCAACUGGAGGAGUUUGAUCUGGAGGAAGAUUUUGAGAUUCUGAGUGUGUAGAAUCCUGGGAACUCAACUUGAAGGUCUGUCUUCCAUCUGGCACCAUAAAAACAUGAACUUAUUGCAUAAAACUUUUCUAGUCAGCAAGUGCCUGAUAUGCCAAUAGCAUACAAACUCAAUAGCAAUCAUGACUGAGCCAAUCACUGUUUCUCAGAAAAACAAAACAAAACAAAACAAAUGACAGUAACCCUUCCCCGGAAAGAAAUAGAACAAUCAUGGAGCCUAGGAGCAGAGAGAUGAGGAGGAGUUCAUUGCUUCCCAGCUUGUGUUAUAUGGCUACAGCAAGUCUUCAGCUGCUGCAAUGAGGAAAUGGGCAUCUGGAAGACAAACAGCAACUCUCAGCUUGCUUCAAGAACCAGCAGAUAAGAGAUGGUUAAGCUGUUCUUCACCCUUUCAGAUGUGACCUCUUUUGGACUAAGCAGCAAUCUGUUCUCUUGCUCAAAUAAUAAAGUGACUGAAUCAGGGAGGAAAAGGUUCUUGUUAAAUUAUUUGAUUGUGUAGUUGAAGUAAUUAUAAUUUAUAUCAAAACGUUUGUCAAAGAAACGAUGUCAAAUAUACACUUCUUGAUCUCCCUUCUGUUUGCGGGGAUCUUACUAUUUGAUGGGUCACUGUCCCCAUUCUUACUGAUACUUUUGUCAGAUAUCACCCUGUCCUUAAAUCAUGAUCACUUAAAUCAGGGGUCAGCAAACUUUUUCUGUAAAGGGCCAGACGGGAAAUAUUUUGGGCUUUGCAGGCCAUGCGGCCUCUGUCACAUCUACUCAACUCUGCUGUUGACAUGCAAAAGCAGCAAUAGACAAUAUGCGUGUAAAUGAGUGUGGCUGUAAUCCAAGAAAACUUUAUUUACAAAAGCAGGUGGAGGGCUGGGUUUGGCCUGCAGGCUGUAGCUUGCCAAUCAGUGACUUAAAUUGUUGAUUUUUGUUUGAUAAAUUAAAAAUAAAUUGUGUUUGAAGUAUACCCUA